GGGUGACGCGACUGGGCCCGUUGUCUGUGUGUGGGACUGAGGGGCCCCGGGGGCGGUGGGGGCUCCCGGUGGGGGCAGCGGUGGGGAGGGAGGGCCUGGACAUGGCGCUGAGGGGCCGCCCCGCGGGAAGAUGAAUAAGGGCUGGCUGGAGCUGGAGAGCGACCCAGGCCUCUUCACCCUGCUCGUGGAAGAUUUCGGUGUCAAGGGGGUGCAAGUGGAGGAGAUCUACGACCUUCAGAGCAAAUGUCAGGGCCCUGUAUAUGGAUUUAUCUUCCUGUUCAAAUGGAUCGAAGAGCGCCGGUCCCGGCGAAAGGUCUCUACCUUGGUGGAUGAUACGUCCGUGAUUGAUGAUGAUAUUGUGAAUAACAUGUUCUUUGCCCACCAGCUGAUACCCAACUCUUGUGCAACUCAUGCCUUGCUGAGCGUGCUCCUGAACUGCAGCAGCGUGGACCUGGGACCCACCCUGAGUCGCAUGAAGGACUUCACCAAGGGUUUCAGCCCUGAGAGCAAAGGAUAUGCGAUUGGCAAUGCCCCGGAGUUGGCCAAGGCCCAUAAUAGCCAUGCCAGGCCCGAGCCACGCCACCUCCCUGAGAAGCAGAAUGGCCUUAGUGCAGUGCGGACCAUGGAGGCGUUCCACUUUGUCAGCUAUGUGCCUAUCACAGGCCGGCUCUUUGAGCUGGAUGGGCUGAAGGUCUACCCCAUUGACCAUGGGCCCUGGGGGGAGGACGAGGAGUGGACAGACAAGGCCCGGCGGGUCAUCAUGGAGCGUAUCGGCCUCGCCACUGCAGGGGAGCCCUACCACGACAUCCGCUUCAACCUGAUGGCAGUGGUGCCCGACCGCAGGAUCAAGUAUGAGGCCAGGCUGCAUGUGCUGAAGGUGAACCGUCAGACAGUACUAGAGGCUCUGCAGCAGCUGAUAAGAGUAACACAGCCAGAGCUGAUUCAGACCCACAAGUCUCAAGAGUCACAGCUGCCUGAGGAGUCCAAGUCAGCCAGCAACAAGUCCCCGCUGGUGCUGGAAGCAAACAGGGCCCCUGCAGCCUCUGAGGGCAACCACACAGAUGGUGCAGAGGAGGCGGCUGGUUCAUGCGCACAAGCCCCAUCCCACAGCCCUCCCAACAAACCCAAGCUAGUGGUGAAGCCUCCAGGCAGCAGCCUCAAUGGGGUUCACCCCAACCCCACUCCCAUUGUCCAGCGGCUGCCGGCCUUUCUAGACAAUCACAAUUAUGCCAAGUCCCCCAUGCAGGAGGAAGAAGACCUGGCGGCAGGUGUGGGCCGCAGCCGAGUUCCAGUCCGCCCACCCCAGCAGUACUCAGAUGAUGAGGAUGACUAUGAGGAUGACGAGGAGGAUGACGUGCAGAACACCAACUCUGCCCUUAGGUAUAAGGGGAAGGGAACAGGGAAGCCAGGGGCAUUGAGCGGUUCUGCUGAUGGGCAACUGUCAGUGCUGCAGCCCAACACCAUCAACGUCUUGGCUGAGAAGCUCAAAGAGUCCCAGAAGGACCUCUCAAUUCCUCUGUCCAUCAAGACUAGCAGCGGGGCUGGGAGUCCGGCUGUGGCAGUGCCCACACACUCGCAGCCCUCACCCACCCCCAGCAAUGAGAGUACAGACACGGCCUCUGAGAUCGGCAGUGCUUUCAACUCGCCACUGCGCUCGCCUAUCCGCUCAGCCAACCCGACGCGGCCCUCCAGCCCUGUCACCUCCCACAUCUCCAAGGUGCUUUUUGGAGAGGAUGACAGCCUGCUGCGUGUUGACUGCAUACGCUACAACCGUGCUGUCCGUGAUCUGGGUCCUGUCAUCAGCACAGGCCUGCUGCACCUGGCUGAGGAUGGGGUGCUGAGUCCCCUGGCGCUGACAGAGGGUGGGAAGGGUUCCUCGCCCUCCAUCAGACCAAUCCAAGGCAGCCAGGGGUCCAGCAGCCCAGUGGAGAAGGAGGUCGUGGAAGCCACGGACAGCAGAGAGAAGACGGGGAUGGUGAGGCCUGGCGAGCCCUUGAGUGGGGAGAAAUACUCACCCAAGCUGCCUAUUGCUCGUGGGGCUUUGUUGCUGGCCCGCCCCGAUCAGAGGUGCAAUGCUGGGUUUUGGCAGGAGCUGCUGGCACUGCUGAAGUGUGUGGAGGCUGAGAUUGCAAACUAUGAGGCGUGCCUCAAGGAGGAGGUAGAGAAGAGGAAGAAGUUCAAGAUUGAUGACCAGAGAAGGACCCACAACUACGAUGAGUUCAUCUGCACCUUUAUCUCCAUGCUGGCUCAGGAAGGCAUGCUGGCCAACCUAGUGGAGCAGAACAUCUCCGUGCGGCGGCGCCAAGGGGUCAGCAUCGGCCGGCUCCACAAGCAGCGGAAGCCUGACCGGCGGAAACGCUCUCGCCCCUACAAGGCCAAGCGCCAGUGAGGACUGCUGGCCCUGACUCUGCAGCCCACUCUUGCCGUGUGGCCCUCACCAGGGUCCUUCCCUGCCCCACUUCCCCUUUUCCCAGUAUUACUGAAUAGUCCCAGCUGGAGAGUCCAGGCCCUGGGAAUGGGAGGAACCAGGCCACAUUCCUUCCAUCGUGCCCUGAGGCCUGACACGGCAGAUCAGCCCCAUAGUGCUCAGGAGGCAGCAUCUGGAGUUGGGGCACAGCGAGGUACUGCAGCUUCCUCCACAGCCGGCUGUGGAGCAGCAGGACCUGGCCCUUCUGCCUGGGCAGCAGAAUAUAUAUUUUACCUAUCAGAGACAUCUAUUUUUCUGGGCUCCAACCCAACAUGCCACCAUGUUGACAUAAGUUCCUACCUGACUAUGCUUUCUCUCCUAGGAGCUGUCCUGGUGGGCCCAGGUCCUUGUAUCAUGCCACGGUCCCAACUACAGGGUCCUAGCUGGGGGCCUGGGUGGGCCCUGGGCUCUGGGCCCUGCUGCUCUAGCCCCAGCCACCAGCCUGUCCCUGUUGUAAGGAAGCCAGGUCUUCUCUCUUCAUUCCUCUUAGGAGAGUGCCAAACUCAGGGACCCAGCACUGGGCUGGGUUGGGAGUAGGGUGUCCCAGUGGGGUUGGGGUGAGCAGGCUGCUGGGAUCCCAUGGCCUGAGCAGAGCAUGUGGGAACUGUUCAGUGGCCUGUGAACUGUCUUCCUUGUUCUAGCCAGGCUGUUCAAGACUGCUCUCCAUAGCAAGGUUCUAGGGCUCUUCGCCUUCAGUGUUGUGGCCCUAGCUAUGGGCCUAAAUUGGGCUCUAGGUCUCUGUCCCUGGCGCUUGAGGCUCAGAAGAGCCUCUGUCCAGCCCCUCAGUAUUACCAUGUCUCCCUCUCAGGGGUAGCAGAGACAGGGUUGCUUAUAGGAAGCUGGCACCACUCAGCUCUUCCUGCUACUCCAGUUUCCUCAGCCUCUGCAAGGCACUCAGGGUGGGGGACAGCAGGAUCAAGACAACCCGUUGGAGCCCCUGUGUUCCAGAGGACCUGAUGCCAAGGGGUAAUGGGCCCAGCAGUGCCUCUGGAGCCCAGGCCCCAACACAGCCCCAUGGCCUCUGCCAGAUGGCUUUGAAAAAGGUGAUCCAAGCAGGCCCCUUUAUCUGUACAUAGUGACUGAGUGGGGGGUGCUGGCAAGUGUGGCAGCUGCCUCUGGGCUGAGCACAGCUUGACCCCUCUAGCCCCUGUAAAUACUGGAUCAAUGAAUGAAUAAAACUCUCCUAAGAAUCUCCUGAGAAA